GUCCCAGUCUCCCGGUGCUUCCCUGAGGCUGAGGCGCCCGGCCUCCCGCCCGCCGCGCUCCAGAUGAAGUGUGAGCACUGCACGCGCAAGGUGAGCGCCGCGGGCCGGGGAGGCGCGCGCCUGGUGCUUGUCCUGUGGGGCUCUGGGCGGCCGAGGUUGGCGGUCCGGGCCCGCCGCUCGCUCGCUUCAGGGCUCUUCAAGGCGCCCCCGGCCUCGGCACCCUGGGCCCGCUCGGCGUGGAGGCGGCCGGCGCGGGGUCCGCUGCGCUCUGCAGGGCGGGUUCGGUCUUCGCGGUUCUCCCUGAACUUGUCCAUCUUUCCCACGCCCGCGAAGCGCGGAAACGCACGGAGACCGAGCCUCUCGUGCCGCGCACCACAGUCCGAGAAUGUAGUAAGAAAACAAAAACUGAUGACCAAGAGAAUGUGUCAGCCGAUGCACCGAGUCCAGCCCAGGAAAAUGGAGAGAAGGGAGAAUUCCACAAGUUGGCUGAUGCCAAGAUAUUUUUGAGCGACUGCCUGGCAUGUGACAGCUGUAUGACUGCAGAGGAAGGAGUCCAACUUUCCCAGCAAAAUGCCAAGGACUUCUUCCGCGUUCUGAACCUUAACAAGAAAUGUGAUACCUCAAAGCACAAAGUGCUGGUAGUGUCUGUGUGUCCUCAAUCUUUGCCUUAUUUUGCUGCUAAAUUCAACCUCAGUGUAACUGAUGCAUCCAGAAGACUCUGUGGUUUCCUCAAAAGUCUUGGGGUGCACUAUGUAUUUGAUACGACGAUAGCUGCGGAUUUUAGUAUCCUGGAGAGUCAAAAAGAAUUCGUGCGUCGCUAUCGCCAGCACAGUGAGGAGGAACGCACCCUGCCCAUGCUGACCUCUGCCUGUCCUGGCUGGGUCCGAUACGCCGAGCGGGUGCUGGGUCGCCCCAUCACUGCCCACCUCUGCACCGCCAAGUCCCCCCAGCAGGUCAUGGGCUCUUUGGUGAAGGAUUAUUUCGCCAGACAGCAGAACCUGUCUCCAGAGAAGAUUUUCCACGUCAUUGUGGCCCCUUGUUAUGACAAGAAGCUGGAGGCUCUUCAGGAAAGCCUUCCCCCUGCUUUGCAUGGCUCCCGGGGCGCUGACUGCGUGUUAACAUCAGGUGAAAUUGCUCAAAUAAUGGAGCAAGGUGACCUCUCAGUGAGAGAUGCUGCCGUCGACACUCUGUUUGGAGACUUGAAGGAGGACAAAGUGACGCGUCAUGAUGGAGCCAGCUCAGACGGGCACCUGGCACACAUCUUCAGACAUGCGGCCAAGGAGCUGUUCAACGAGGAUGUGGAGGAGGUCACUUACCGAGCCCUGAGAAACAAAGACUUCCAAGAGGUCACCCUUGAGAAGAACGGAGAGGUGGUGUUACGCUUUGCUGCAGCCUAUGGCUUUCGAAACAUCCAGAACAUGAUCCUGAAGCUUAAGAAGGGCAAGUUCCCAUUCCACUUUGUGGAGGUCCUCGCCUGUGCUGGAGGAUGCUUAAAUGGCAGAGGCCAAGCCCAGACUCCAGACGGACAUGCGGAUAAGGCCCUGCUGCGGCAGAUGGAAGGCAUUUACGCUGACAUCCCUGUGCGGCGUCCGGAGUCCAGUGCACACGUGCAGGAGCUGUACCAGGAGUGGCUGGAGGGGAUCAACUCCCCCAAGGCCCGAGAGGUGCUGCAUACCACGUACCAGAGCCAGGAGCGUGGCACACACAGCCUGGACAUCAAGUGGUGAAGUCAGGCCAGGGCCUUCCAGCUGCUCUUGGGGCCAGAGCCAAGAGCCUCUCAGUAGAGGGAGGGGCUGCCCUGAGUGGAGUAUUAAAGACACUUAAGAAAACCGCUCAAUGGAUUACUUUGGUUUCUCCGAGUUCCCUGCUACCCCGUUUAUUGGAGGCCCCUCAGGCAGUUUCAUGUGGUGCUAUCUUCAUAAUAGGUGUGGGAUUGGAACUUUUUUUUUCUUUUUUUUUUUUUGAGACGGAGUCUCACUCUGUCACCCAGGCUGGAGUGCAAUGGCGCAAUCUCAGCUCACUGCAACCUCUGCCUCCCGGGUUCAAGCGAUUCUCUUGCCCCAGCCUCCCGAGUAGCUGGGACUAACGCGCACACCACCAUGCCCAGCUAAUUUUUGUAUUUUUAGUAGAGAUGGGGUUUCACUAUGUUGGCCAGGCUGGUAUUGAAUUCCUGACCUCCUGAUCCACCCGCCUUGGCCUCCCAAAGUGCCAGGACUGCAGGCAUGAGCCACCGUGCCUGGCAGAUUGGAACGUUUUAACAUGAGAGGAGCACUUCCCCAAUUUAUCCCUUCAUCCUAAGAUUGUGAAAAAGUCCCAAAGAGUGGGAAUGGAGACAGACUACUGUAUUUUAGGUUUAAAAAGAAAAAUCCAGAAAGUGUCCUGUGAAGAGCUAGGACCCCCAGAGGUUCUAAUGCACAUGACUUGAAGGUGAUUUGAUGUGGGAGUGAGGGCAGAGGGUGGGGUGGCUGUGCCUGUGGACUCCUGUGGCCCUGGGGUUGUUAGGGCAGGCAGUCCACAGUCCCAGAUCCCUGCCCAUUUUGGCUCUUUCUUUUACCCACUCAUAUUUUCCUUGAAAAUGUUUUUGCCAGAACAUUAAUAACUGUCAGCCUUUUAGAAUCAGGAGACUUACGUACAAAUCUGGAUUUUCAGCUUUUCUUAGAAAAACUGUAGUUUCUGACAACAGUAGGCCCCAUUCCUCACAGCCAGUCACCACCCUCCUCCCAUUCCUCACAGCCAGUCACCACCCUCCUGGACCAUACUCGGCCCUGGGCCAUUCCUCACAGCCAGUCACCACCCUCCUCCCAUUCCUCACAGCCAGUCACCACCCUCCUGGACCACACUCGGCCCUGGGCCAUUCCUCACAGCCAGUCACCACCCUCCUGGACCAUACUCAGGGCCCUGGAGGCCUGGCAACCCAGGCCCCAACUCAAACUUGUACAUUCAGUCUUUCAGUCGGACUCGCACUGGGGCAAGGGUGACAGACACGAGAAUGGAAAAUUGAGAAGGCUGCCCGCACCAGCUGGGUGGGUGCAGGGGGCCCCAGCUCAUCAUCAGCACUGUCGUGGGGUGGGAGUCGGGGGUAAAGGUUCCGUCUGACCCUGAGGGGUUGAGGAUAUUCAGGUGGUCCAGCCUCCCGCAGAAGACUUCCCUGUCACCCUUGGCAGACAGGUUUCUUCUCACACGGCCCUGGCCCAUCCACUCGCCAUGAAGCCCUCUGUGCUCAGGGUGAUGGAGCCCCCUCCAUUCUGGCACUGCACUGUGGGCAUGAGCUUGCCUUAAAAAGAAAGGAGAGGCCAGGCACGGUGGCUCGUGCCCUAUAAUCCCAGCACACUGGGAGGCCAAGGUGGGAGGAUUGCUGGAGUCCAGGAGUUUCUACAUGGGAGACUCUGUCUCUACAAAUUUUUUUUUUUUUUUUGAGACAGAGUCUCACUUUGUCACCCAGGCUGGAGUUCAGUGGCGUGAUCUCGGCUCACAGCAACCUCCGCCUCCUGGGUUCAAGCGAUUCUCCUGCCUCAGCCUCUGGAGUAGCUGGGAUUACAGGCGCGCGCCACCGCGCCUGGCUAAUUGUAUUCUUAGUUGAGACGGGUUUCGCCAUGUUGAUCGGGCCGGUCAGGCUGGAAUUUCUGACCUCAGGUGAUCCAACCACCUCAGCCUCCCAAAAUGCUGGGAUUACAGGCGUGAGCCACUGCACCUGGCAAAAAAUUUUUUUUUAAAAAGGAGAAAGCAGUUUAACCACAAACAGUGAAACAGAGCUGGCAGACGCCUGAAACUCCAUGGAACCAUGCAGCUGUACCCUAGGGCUCCUCCCAGGAAAAGAGAGAUGUCAACGUGGCCCAAGGUGUCCUGAAGCACUGGGAUUGGAUUAACUCGAGCGAUGGCCUUCCCAGCCCUCCGUGCUGCAGAGCCUCUGCUCGCUAGGCUGCCUUCAUCUCACUCUGUGUGCUGUGCCUGUGCACCUGUCUUGUCAAUAACUGCAUAUAUUGUGUUGCGUUGCCUGUCUUGCUGGAUAACUGCAUAUAUUGUGUUCAGUUGUGUAUUUGUUUUGCUUUCAGUCUAUAUACAGUUGGGUUUCCAACCUCUGAUUCUGGAAUAAACAGUUGCAGCGUG